CUAUUGAAGCCACCUGCUCAGGACAAUGAAAUUCUUCAGUUACAUUCUGGUUUAUCGCCGAUUUCUCUUCGUGGUUUUCACUGUGUUGGUUUUACUACCUCUGCCCAUCGUCCUCCACACCAAGCUUAUUCUGACUUUUCCAAGAUGAAGAUGAAGAGCAGGCCAGUGGCAUGGGCCAGAUGCAGUCAGAUGACUGACUGACCAGGAGGGCCUCCGUCCAGUGACCAGUCUCAGAAUUUAAAGGACCCUUCCCCCUUACUUAUGCUUGUACUCAGCCCAGGAAGCAGAAUGUGCCUACACACUCUUUGUGGUCGCCACAUUUUGGCUCACAGAAGCAUUGCCUCUGUCGGUAACAGCUUUGCUACCUAGUUUAAUGUUACCCAUGUUUGGGAUCAUGCCUUCUAAGAAGGUGGCAUCUGCUUAUUUCAAGGAUUUUCACUUACUGCUAAUUGGAGUUAUCUGUUUAGCAACAUCCAUAGAAAAAUGGAAUUUGCACAAGAGAAUUGCUCUGAAAAUGGUGAUGAUGGUUGGUGUAAAUCCUGCAUGGCUGACGCUGGGGUUCAUGAGCAGCACUGCCUUUUUGUCUAUGUGGCUCAGCAACACCUCGACGGCUGCCAUGGUGAUGCCCAUUGCGGAGGCUGUAGUGCAGCAGAUCAUCAAUGCAGAAGCAGAGGUCGAGGCCACUCAGAUGACUUACUUCAACGGAUCAACCAACCACGGACUAGAAAUUGAUGAAAGUGUUAAUGGACAUGAAAUAAAUGAGAGGAAAGAGAAAACAAAACCAGUUCCAGGAUACAAUAAUGAUACAGGGAAAAUUUCAAGCAAGGUGGAGUUGGAAAAGUACUUGCAAGUGAGGUGACCAAAAAACAGCUUUAGACUCUUAAACUUAGUGUUUAAAAUGAGAAGGCUGAGAGACAGUCUGCUUAUGGAGAAAGUUGGAGUAUUUCCCCAGUGCCCCAACCCCCUGCCACUUGUACCAUCACAGUCGAAAGAAGGGAAGAGUCUCCUACUUAACAAGGAAGAGGAAGAAUCAAACCAACAAAGGGUGUUUACAGGGUCAUGGGUGAGAAAAAGAAUGAAGUUGCUUUUGGCUUACACCCUAGAAAGUCAUCUCUUAAAUAAAACACUUACAUUUGGACUAGUGAUUCCCCAAGUGAAACCAUUUCAGGAUGUGCCAUUGUCCAAGAACUCAGGCAUGAGAACCAAAUAUCGAACAAAGAAGGGCCACGUGACACGUAAACUUACGUGUUUGUGCAUUGCCUACUCUUCUACCAUUGGUGGACUGACAACAAUCACUGGUACCUCCACCAACUUGAUCUUUGCAGAGUAUUUCAAUACACGCUAUCCUGACUGUCGUUGCCUCAACUUUGGAUCAUGGUUUACGUUUUCCUUCCCAGCUGCCCUUAUCAUUCUACUCUUAUCCUGGAUCUGGCUUCAGUGGCUUUUCCUAGGAUUCAAUUUUAAGGAGAUGUUCAAAUGUGGCAAAACCAAAACAGUCCAACAAAAAGCUUGUGCUGAGGUGAUUAAGCAAGAAUACCAAAAGCUUGGGCCAAUAAGGUAUCAAGAAAUUGUGACCUUGGUCCUCUUCAUUAUAAUGGCUCUGCUAUGGUUUAGUCGAGACCCCGGAUUUGUUCCUGGUUGGUCUGCACUUUUUUCAGAGUACCCUGGUUUUGCUACAGAUUCAACUGUUGCUUUACUUAUAGGGCUGCUAUUCUUUCUUAUCCCAGCUAAGACACUGACUAAAACUACACCUACAGGAGAAAUUGUUGCUUUUGAUUACUCUCCACUGAUUACUUGGAAAGAAUUCCAGUCAUUCAUGCCCUGGGAUAUAGCCAUUCUUGUUGGUGGAGGGUUUGCCCUGGCAGAUGGUUGUGAGGAGUCUGGAUUAUCUAAGUGGAUAGGAAAUAAAUUAUCUCCUCUGGGUUCAUUACCAGCAUGGCUAAUAAUUCUGAUAUCUUCUUUGAUGGUGACAUCUUUAACUGAGGUAGCCAGCAAUCCAGCUACCAUUACACUCUUUCUCCCAAUAUUAUCUCCAUUGGCCGAAGCCAUUCAUGUGAACCCUCUUUAUAUUCUGAUACCUUCUACUCUGUGUACUUCAUUUGCAUUCCUCCUACCAGUAGCAAAUCCACCCAAUGCUAUUGUCUUUUCAUAUGGUCAUCUGAAAGUCAUUGACAUGGUUAAAGCUGGACUUGGUGUCAACAUUGUUGGUGUUGCUGUGGUUAUGCUUGGCAUAUGUACUUGGAUUGUACCCAUGUUUGACCUCUACACUUACCCUUCGUGGGCUCCUGCUAUGAGUAAUGAGACCAUGCCAUAAUAAGCACAAAAUUUCUGACUAUCUUGCGGUAAUUUCUGGAAGACAUUAAUGAUUGACUGUAAAAUGUGGCUCUAAAUAACUAAUGACACACAUUUAAAUCAGUUAUGGUGUAGCUGCUGCAAUUCCUGUGAAUACCCGAAACCUGCUGUUAUAACUCAGAGUCCAUAUUUGUUAUUGCAGUGCAACUAAAGAGCAUCUAUGUGCCUUCAUCAAGAAGCCCAUGUUUUGAGAUUUUGCUCAUGAACCAUCUGCAACUUGCUUCAUCAUAAGAAUAAUUUAUAACUUGACCUUCAAAGAGAUUAGAGCAUUUGUUUCAUCUUACAGUUGGAGUUCAAUGUAACAUUUUAAAUGCAAUUUAUUAUUUCAGAAAUUUCCCAUGAAACUAAAAAUAGAAAAUAAGAUAUACAAGUUAAUUCGGUACUUGGAUAAAUCAUUUCUGCAUUGUUGUUCCAGAGAAUUUGCUGAGAAAUCAAAGCCAUGGUCAUCUGGUGAUGAAGAGAAAAGUUUAAUCUAAAUGAUAUGUGCAUUUCCUCAUUUAAAAAAUCCAAUUGGAUUAUUCUUAAUAUAUACAUGUAAUAUGAAAAUUGAGAUUGAAGCACUAAUUCCAAAAUUAUGGCUGAAUAUACUAAAUAACAGAAAAGUUACAGAUAAGAAUUUAUUUCUACUGAACUCUAUAGUUAGUGUAAUAUAAUUCAUAUUUUUAUGAUAUUGGCACACUGAGAAAUUCAUUUUGUAGAGCUAUGGAUAAGGCUUGCUAUGAUUUGCACUAUUAGUACAGUAUAGUUAGAAAGGAAAGCUGAACACUAUAAAACUAUUAACAUAUUUUCGUAUAUGAGUAACAACUUUGCUUAAGUGUUUAUCUUAGUUCAGAAAUACAUAAUGUCAUAUGUUAAAAAUAAAGAGAUGUAGAAAUCUAAAUGAAUUAUCACUGUGUAUACAGACAGAAAAAUCACAUAACUCUGGUGUGUUAACAUUGCAAUGAAAAAAUGAAAAAAAGAAGGAAAAAAGAAUAAGAAUGAAAACUGCUGACGUAUUACAAAACAGAAAAAUAAAUGAUUUAAAAUCAAAUCAAAAAGAAAAAACUAAACAUUUAAACAAAAAUGGGAUAAGAAUAGUCUUCUAGAAGUGAGGAUGCGAAAAAGAAUGAGUUUCCAAUUACCCUGAUGUGACAAUUACACAUUGUAGACAGGUAGCAAAAUAUCACAUACACCCCCAAAAUAUGUACAAAUAUUAUAUAUCAAUAAAUAAAUUUUUAAAGAGUAAGUGCUAUUGGCAUUCCAAAAUUCAGCUAAAGGAAAAAUGAUCAAAAACAAAGUAAGGUGCACAGUUAGCAAAAGAUGCAGAUGUUAUAUCACAGCAAUUCUCAUGCUAAAAAUACAACAAAAGACAAAGCAAAAAAUAAACCUUUGCUUUUUUUUUUUUUUUUUUUUUUUUGAGACGGAGUCUCGCUCUGUCGCCCAGGCUGGAGUGCAGUGGCGGGAUCUCGGCUCACUGCAAGCUCCGCCUCCCAGGUUCACGCCAUUCUCCUGCCUCAGCCAAACCUUUGCUAUUUUUAAUCUUCGUUGGCACUUUCCAGCUGUUACUGACCUUGUCAUUUUUUAUUCAAAUAAGAUUAUUUACAAACUUAUUCUUGAAACUAAAUAUAGUAAAGAGGGUUUUUAAAAUAAUAUUUAACAUACGAAUUAUUAAUUGGCCAUGUUCAUUAUUUAUCUAUGUUUAUUAAUGGGCCAAUGCAAAAAAUCAUUUUUUCAAAGAAAAAUUUGUCCAUGUAAAGCUUAAAUUAUAAUAUUGCUGCUUUGUAUAACUCUUCUAUGUUUAUUCUAUUCAUUUGUUCCUUUCCCUACCAUAUUUUACACAUGUAUUUAUAAUCUGUAGUAUUUAUUACAUUUCUGCUUUUUUCUAGUCAUUCAAUUUAUCACUGCUGAAUUGCAUCAGAUCAUGGAUGCAUUUUUAUUAUGAAAAAAUAAAAUGACUUUUCAAAUUA